UUUGAGCCUGGGCUGAAACUGCGGGUGUGACCCCCCCGUGGUGGCUCUGGGUGUCUGCGGAGGAGCUGGGGGCGGAAGCAUGAGGCUAACGGCUUGGCUUCAGUGAACGCACCGGGAUGUGCAGGCCGGGAGGUAGAGGCAGGCUGAUGGGGGAGGGAACGAGCAGCCUGUGAGACGGGGUGACGGCGGCUACCAGCCCGGGCGGGCACCGGGACUGGAAGAGUUGCCUGAGCAGCCGGCUGGUCCGGCGGCCAGGCUAGGGCGGGGGCGAGCGCCCAGUUGAGCCUGCUGGGGCUGGAGGAGCGAGAAGGGUUUUCUUCACAUUUCAGAGCGAACCAGACGGGGACAGUAAGGUUUGGAGGAAGGGGGAUCGUUGGAAGUAGCAAGAAGUGGAGAGAAUCUGGCAAUAGACGAGAAACCGAAAGAAUCAGAAAGAAGUCUAUGUGAGUAGCUGAAAGCAUUGGGUGACCAGAAAGAAGGUCGGUGUAAGUGAAGGAAGAGUGAGGUGUGGCUGGAUCAAAGGGCUAAGAGAAGCGGGUCUGUGUAAGUGGAUGUGAGUGAGGAUCAAGGAAAAGCCGUGGAAGUGGCCGGGGGUCGGGGCCGCAGAAGUGCCAGACGGGGCCGGAAAGCAGCCGAGCGGAGUUCAAAUUUGAGAGCGUUUGGAAAUUGGAAGACUUGGUGGCGAACGAGGGUCAGGACCUGCAUCCUGCCUCAGAGAGUUAUCGACGUAUCCGGAAUGUGGGAUCAGAGGCUGGUGAGGUUGGCCCUGUUGCAGCAUCUGCGGGCCUUCUAUGGUAUUAAGGUGAAGGGUGUCCGUGGGCAGUGCGAUCGCAGGAGACAUGAAACAGCAGCCACGGAAAUAGGGGGUAAAAUAUUUGGAGUACCUUUUAAUGCACUGCCCCAUUCUGCUGUACCAGAAUAUGGACACAUUCCAAGCUUUCUUGUCGAUGCUUGCACAUCUUUAGAAGACCAUAUUCAUACCGAAGGGCUUUUUCGGAAAUCAGGAUCUGUGAUUCGCCUAAAAGCACUAAAGAAUAAAGUGGAUCAUGGUGAAGGUUGCCUAUCUUCUGCACCUCCUUGUGAUAUUGCGGGACUUCUUAAGCAGUUUUUUAGGGAACUGCCAGAGCCCAUUCUCCCAGCUGAUUUGCAUGAAGCACUUUUGAAAGCUCAACAGUUAGGCACAGAGGAAAAGAAUAAAGCUACACUGUUGCUCUCCUGUCUUCUGGCUGACCACACAGUUCAUGUAUUAAGAUACUUCUUUAACUUUCUCAGGAAUGUUUCUCUUAGAUCCAGUGAGAAUAAGAUGGACAGCAGCAAUCUUGCAGUAAUAUUUGCACCGAAUCUUCUUCAGACAAGUGAAGGACAUGAAAAGAUGUCUUCUAACACAGAAAAGAAGCUACGAUUACAGGCUGCAGUAGUACAGACUCUUAUCGAUUAUGCAUCAGAUAUUGGGCGUGUACCAGAUUUUAUCCUGGAAAAGAUACCAGCCAUGUUGGGUAUUGAUGGUCUCUGUGCUACUCCAUCACUGGAAGGCUUUGAAGAAGGUGAAUAUGAAACUCCUGGUGAAUAUAAGAGAAAGAGAAGACAAAGUGUAGGAGAUUUUGUUAGUGGAGCACUAAAUAAAUUUAAACCUAACAGAACACCUUCUAUUACACCUCAAGAAGAAAGAAUUGCCCAGCUAUCUGAAUCACCAGUGAUUCUUACACCAAAUGCUAAGCGUACAUUGCCAGUAGAUUCUUCUCAUGGUUUCUCAAGUAAGAAAAGGAAGUCCAUCAAGCACAAUUUUAACUUUGAGCUGUUGCCAAGUAAUCUCUUCAAUAGCAGUUCUACACCGGUAUCAGUUCACAUCGAUACAAGCUCAGAAGGGUCAUCUCAGAGUUCACUCUCUCCUGUACUCAUUGGUGGAAACCAUUUGAUCACUGCAGGUGUGCCAAGGCGAAGUAAAAGAAUUGCAGGCAAAAAAGUUUGCAGGUUGACAAUGGUCUCCAGGAUGGUCUCUACCAUGCUAUCUGGCCUACUGUUUUGGCUGGCAUCUGGAUGGACUCCAGCAUUUGCUUACAGCCCCCGGACCCCUGACCGGGUCUCAGAAGCAGAUAUCCAGAGGCUGCUUCAUGGUGUUAUGGAGCAAUUGGGCAUUGCCAGGCCCCGAGUGGAAUAUCCAGCUCACCAGGCCAUGAAUCUUGUGGGCCCCCAGAGCAUUGAAGGUGGAGCUCAUGAAGGACUUCAGCAUUUGGGUCCUUUUGGCAACAUCCCCAACAUCGUGGCAGAGUUGACUGGAGACAACAUUCCUAAGGACUUUAGUGAGGAUCAGGGGUACCCAGACCCUCCAAAUCCCUGUCCUGUUGGAAAAACAGAUGAUGGAUGUCUAGAAAACACCCCUGACACUGCAGAGUUCAGUCGAGAGUUCCAGUUGCACCAGCAUCUCUUUGAUCCGGAACAUGACUAUCCAGGCUUGGGCAAGUGGAACAAGAAACUCCUUUACGAGAAGAUGAAGGGAGGAGAGAGACGAAAGCGGAGGAGUGUCAAUCCAUAUCUACAAGGACAGAGACUGGAUAAUGUUGUUGCAAAGAAGUCUGUCCCCCAUUUUUCAGAUGAGGAUAAGGAUCCAGAGUAAAGAGAAGAUGCUAGACGAAAACCCACAUUACCUGUUAGGCCUCAGCAUGGCUUAUGUGCACGUGUAAAUGGAGUCCCUGUGAAUGACAGCAUGUUUCUUACAUAGAUAAUUAUGGAUACAAAGCAGCUGUAUGUAGAUAGUGUAUUGUCUUCACACCGAUGAUUCUGCUUUUUGCUAAAUUAGAAUAAGAGCUUUUUUGUUUCUUGGGUUUUUAAAAUGUGAAUCUGCAAUGAUCAUAAAAAUUAAAAUGUGAAUGUCAACAAUAAAAAGCAAGACUAUGAAAGGCUCAGAUUUCUUGCAGUUUAAAAUGGUGUCUGAGGUUGUACUAUUUUGGCCAAGUCUGUAGAAAGCUGUCAUUUGAUUUUGAUUAUGUAGUUCAUCCAGCCCUUGGGCAUUGUUAUACACCAGUAAAGAAGGCUGUACUCAAGAGGAGGAGCUGACACAUUUCACUUGGCUGCGUCUUAAUAAACAUGAAUGCAAGCAUUGGCA